GGCGCGCGCCCCGCACGCGCGCCCCCGCACGCGCAUAACGGCUUGGCUUACCUGUAACGGGUACGCUUCGCUUCGCGUUCCUCGCUUGGCCUUGCGUUCCUAGCUUGGCUUGGCUGUUAGUAGCUUUGCCUGGUGUUUCUUGCUUGGAUUGGCGUUUCCUCCCUCGCAUUCCUUUGCUGGACUUGACCUUUUCUCUGCUGGGUUUGGCAUUCCCUUGACUGGGCUGGGUGUUUCCUUGGGAGGGGGGGCUUGGCCUUUCCUGGGGUGGGCGUGGGGUCCCCCUGGUGGGCGUGGGCUUUCCCCGGGUGGGUGUGGGUUUUCCCUGGGUGGGGUGGGCUGGGCUCCCUUGCUGGGGUUGGCAAGUUUUGGCUGGGAUUGACCUUUCUCUUCAAACAGAUUGGAAACCCAGGGUUUCCUGCUAGUUGGUGAAACUGGUUGGUAGACGCGAUCUGUUCGCUACUACCGGCCUCCCCUGGCUGUUAAAAGCAGAUGGUGGCUGAGGUUUGUUCAAUGCCCGCUGCCUCUGCUGUGAAGAAGCCAUUUGAUCUCAGGAGCAAGAUGGGCAAGUGGUGCCACCACCGCUUCCCCUGCUGCAGGGGGAGCGGCACGAGCAAUGUGGGCACUUCUGGAGACCAUGACGACUCCUUUAUGAAGACACUCAGGAGCAAGAUGGGCAAGUGGUGCUGUCACUGCUUCCCCUGCUGCAGGGGGAGCGGCAAGAGCAACGUGGGCACUUGGGGAGACUACGACGACAGCGCCUUCAUGGAGCCGAGGUACCACGUCCGUCGAGAAGAUCUGGACAAGCUCCACAGAGCUGCCUGGUGGGGUAAAGUCCCCAGAAAGGAUCUCAUCGUCAUGCUCAGGGACACUGACAUGAACAAGAGGGACAAGCAAAAGAGGACUGCUCUACAUUUGGCCUCUGCCAAUGGAAAUUCAGAAGUAGUACAACUCCUGCUGGACAGACGAUGUCAACUUAACGUCCUUGACAACAAAAAAAGGACAGCUCUGAUAAAGGCCGUACAAUGCCAGGAAGAUGAAUGUGUGUUAAUGUUGCUGGAACAUGGCGCUGAUGGAAAUAUUCAAGAUGAGUAUGGAAAUACCGCUCUACACUAUGCUAUCUACAAUGAAGAUAAAUUAAUGGCCAAAGCACUGCUCUUAUAUGGUGCUGAUAUUGAAUCAAAAAACAAGUGUGGCCUCACACCACUUUUGCUUGGCGUACAUGAACAAAAACAGGAAGUGGUGAAAUUUUUAAUCAAGAAAAAAGCUAAUUUAAAUGCACUUGAUAGAUAUGGAAGAACUGCCCUCAUACUUGCUGUAUGUUGUGGAUCAGCAAGUAUAGUCAAUCUUCUACUUGAGCAAAAUGUUGAUGUAUCUUCUCAAGAUCUAUCUGGACAGACAGCCAGAGAGUAUGCUGUUUCUAGUCAUCAUCAUGUAAUUUGUGAAUUACUUUCUGACUAUAAAGAAAAACAGAUGCUAAAAAUCUCUUCUGAAAACAGCAAUCCAGAACAAGACUUAAAGCUGACAUCAGAGGAAGAGUCACAAAGGCUUAAAGUCAGUGAAAAUAGCCAGCCAGAGAAAAUGUCUCAAGAACCAGAAAUAAAUAAGGACUGUGAUAGAGAGGUUGAAGAAGAAAUAAAGAAGCAUGGAAGUAAUCCUGUGGGAUUACCAGAAAACCUGACUAAUGGUGCCAGUGCUGGCAAUGGUGAUGAUGGAUUAAUUCCACAAAGGAAGAGCAGAAAACCUGAAAAUCAGCAAUUUCCUGACACUGAGAAUGAAGAGUAUCACAGUGACGAACAAAAUGAUACCCAGAAACAACUUUCUGAAGAACAGAACACUGGAAUAUCACAAGAUGAGAUUCUGACUAAUAAACAAAAGCAGAUAGAAGUGGCUGAAAAGGAAAUGAAUUCUGAGCUUUCUCUUAGUCAUAAGAAAGAAGAAGAUCUCUUGCGUGAAAACAGCAUGUUGCGGGAAGAAAUUGCCAAGCUAAGACUGGAACUAGAUGAAACAAAACAUCAGAACCAGCUAAGGGAAAAUAAAAUUUUGGAGGAAAUUGAAAGUGUAAAAGAAAAACUUCUAAAGACUAUACAACUGAAUGAAGAAGCAUUAACGAAAACCAGUAUUUAAGUACAGUGGACAGCUUAGG